GCAACACGUGGGGGCGGUGCCGGUCGGAGGGCUCCUAGUGCGCCAGGUUGUGGGAAGUGAGGCUGGCGGUGGCGACAACCGAGGAGGAGGGGCGGGACGCCGUGGAGCACGGCGACCGGCUGAGCGUCAUGGAGGGCUCAGGGGAGCAGCCGGGCCCACAACCACAGCAUCCCGGAGACCACCGCAUCCGCGACGGCGACUUCGUGGUGCUGAAACGUGAAGAUGUGUUUAAAGCAGUACAAGUCCAGCGGAGAAAAAAAGUAACUUUCGAAAAACAGUGGUUCUACCUGGAUAACGUCAUUGGCCAUAGUUAUGGAACUGCAUUUGAAGUGACCAGUGGAGGAAGUCUACAGCCCAAGAAGAAGAGGGAAGAGCCUACUGCAGAGACUAAAGAAGCGGGCACUGAUAAUCGAAAUAUAGUUGAUGAUGGGAAAUCUCAGAAACUUACUCAAGAUGACAUAAAAGCUUUGAAGGACAAGGGCAUUAAAGGAGAGGAAAUAGUUCAGCAGUUAAUUGAAAAUAGUACAACAUUCCGAGACAAGACAGAAUUUGCCCAAGAUAAAUAUAUUAAAAAGAAGAAAAAAAAAUAUGAAGCCAUCAUUACUGUUGUGAAGCCAUCCACCCGUAUUCUUUCAAUUAUGUAUUAUGCAAGAGAACCUGGAAAAAUUAACCACAUGAGAUACGAUACACUAGCCCAGAUGUUGACGUUGGGAAAUAUCCGUGCUGGCAACAAAAUGAUUGUGAUGGAAACGUGUGCAGGCUUGGUGCUGGGUGCAAUGAUGGAACGAAUGGGAGGUUUUGGCUCCAUUAUUCAGCUAUACCCUGGAGGAGGACCUGUUCGGGCAGCAACAGCAUGUUUUGGAUUUCCCAAAUCUUUUCUCAGUGGUCUUUAUGAAUUCCCUCUCAACAAAGUGGACAGUCUUCUACAUGGAACAUUUUCUGCCAAGAUGUUAUCUUCAGAGCCAAAAGACAGUGCUUUGGUUGAAGAAAGUAAUGGCACACUGGAGGAAAAACAGGCUUCUGAACAAGAGAAUGAAGACAGCAUGGCAGAGGCCCCAGAGAGCAACCACCCAGAAGACCAGGAAACAAUGGAAACAAUUUCUCAAGAUCCAGAACAUAAGGGGCCUAAAGAGAGAGGAAGCAAAAAAGAUUAUAUUCAGGAAAAACAGAGGAGACAAGAAGAGCAGAGGAAAAGACAUUUAGAGGCUGCCGCUCUGCUGAGUGAAAGAAACGCAGAUGGUUUAAUUGUAGCUAGUCGUUUCCACCCCACUCCCCUGCUGCUGUCUUUGCUGGACUUUGUGGCCCCUUCAAGGCCGUUUGUGGUCUACUGUCAGUACAAAGAGCCUCUGUUGGAAUGCUACACAAAACUGCGGGAGAGGGGAGGGGUCAUCAACCUCAGGCUGUCUGAAACCUGGCUCAGAAAUUAUCAGGUUUUGCCAGAUCGAAGUCAUCCUAAACUGCUGAUGAGUGGAGGUGGGGGUUAUCUUCUCUCCGGCUUCACCGUUGCCAUGGACAACCUUAAAGCAGACACCAGCCUCAAAUCUAAUGCAAGCACUUUAGAAUCACACGAGACUGAGGAGCCUGCAGCUAAAAAACGAAAAUGCCCAGAGUCUGACUCUUAACCCUUUUGAGAAUUGCUCUGAAUUUUGUUCUCAGGCAUUAUACAGUUAGUAAUUAAACUUUAAAUGCCAUUACUACUUGUUUUUUCAUAUCCCAAGAAUAAGAACAUGUCUAUGUACCCGUUUCUAGGAAGGAGGAGUAUAUGCCUUUUGUCUAUUUCUGACACAGAUGCAUUUGGUCUGUCAAAACUGCAACCAUGGGGUAUGUAGUAUGACCAACUGCAUUUAACAAAACUCCUCUAAGUACUUCUAAAUAUUCUGUGCAAAUAUCUUGAGAACUUCAACAUCCUAAAAAUGUGUUUCUACAAGACUUUAUAUUUUAAGCUAAGUGGAAUAAUACAACGUAACUAAAACAUGGCGGGUACCGAAAGGAGGGCAAUUCAUGGAAGAAAUUUCCUCUGUUCAUUCCGUUCUCUUCAACCUAAGCAAUAUGGAUGUGUGAGUGUGUGAUUUAUUAUGGUACCAAAAAUGUCCACCUUCUUUCCUGCAGCGGAAUAAGCUUUUUUGAAAUGCUGAGGUUUUAUUUUAAUAGUUGACAACCUGGGAAAGUUCUGAGUAUUUAUUUUACUGCUCUUUUUUGUGCAUAGAAAGGUUUAGUAGGGUACUUUUUUGCAUUAAUUUGCCAAUACUCUUAUUCUUUGUUCUAAAUAAAGUGACUAGAAUUUUUGUGUACUAUUCAAUUAAAGGAAACAAAUGUCUUUUCCCCCUCUAUGGUCUUAUGGAUACACAUUUGCACACACACACAUAUGUAUAUAGAUGUUGGUAUAUAUACACACAUAUAUUUAUAUAUACACAGAUAUAUACAUACACAUGCAAGUGGAGACAUAGAUUGUACCACCUGUAUGAAUAUGUAUGUACACAUGGGGACAGAAAGAGUGUGCAGUCUAUUUGAACUGUAUCAAAGUCUUGUGCAGGACUUAGACCAAUUCUCAUUGUAUUAGUGUCAUUCCUUGUCAAAUGUCCCUAAAGUGCCUUUCUUGAUUAUUAAUGCUGAAGAACUCUGUCAUGAUUAGAUGGUUACCCUUUCUAAGCUCUGAAAAACUCUAAUCAUUUGAUCAUGUGCUGUAGCAAAGAAAGUGUUUAGAAUCAGCCAAGGCUCUUGUUCAUUUGAGAGAUUGAGUCUUGCUCACUGGAACAUGGUCAUCGUUUGCGUUGCUCCUGUCAUAGAAUAGGCCUGUAUCAUACAGCAAGGAACAUCUCAGAAAAAAAAUUUUUUUUCCAAAUAGCAUGUGCUAUGCCAAUGUGAUUACUAAGUACAAUUUUGAGUCCUUUAUCCUAAUUGCUAUUAAAGAAUAAAAAUGUCGGCCGGG